GCCCGCUUACGCAGUUCCUCCCGGGGUCGGAGGCCGAUUCGCCGUGUGGCGGGUUCGAGUCCCGCCUCCUGACUCUGGCCUCUAGUCCCUGAGUCCCGGGCGGGCUGCAUUCGUCGGGGAAACCUCUCCUCGACCAGGGGCACCUCUACUCGACCAGGGGCGACGGCGUACUUUGGGCUUCAUCAUGGAGGACUACCUGCAGGGUUGUCGAGCUGCUCUGCAGGAGUCCCGACCUCUACAUGUUGUGCUGGGAAAUGAAGCCUGUGAUUUGGACUCCACAGUGUCUGCUCUUGCCCUGGCUUUUUACCUAGCAAAGACAACUGAGGCUGAGGAAGUCUUUGUGCCAGUUUUAAAUAUAAAACGUUCUGAACUACCUCUGCGAGGUGACAUUGUCUUCUUUCUUCAGAAGGUUCAUAUUCCAGAGAGUAUCUUGAUUUUUCGGGAUGAGAUUGACCUCCAUGCAUUAUACCAGGCUGGCCAACUCACCCUCAUCCUUGUCGACCAUCAUAUCUUAUCCAAAAGUGACACAGCCCUAGAGGAGGCAGUAGCAGAGGUGCUAGACCAUCGACCCAUCGAGCCGAAACACUGCCCUCCCUGCCAUGUUUCAGUUGAGCUGGUGGGGUCCUGUGCUACCCUGGUGACCGAGAGAAUCCUGCAGGGGGCACCAGAGAUCUUGGACAGGCAAACUGCAGCCCUUCUGCAUGGAACCAUCAUCCUGGACUGUGUCAACAUGGACCUUAAAAUUGGAAAGGCAACCCCAAAGGACAGCAAAUAUGUGGAGAAACUAGAGGCCCUUUUCCCAGACCUACCCAAGAGAAAUGAUAUAUUUGAUUCCCUACAAAAGGCAAAGUUUGAUGUAUCAGGACUGACCACUGAGCAGAUGCUGAGAAAAGACCAGAAGACUAUCUAUAGACAAGGCGUCAAGGUGGCCAUUAGUGCAAUAUAUAUGGAUUUGGAGGCCUUUCUGCAGAGGUCUAACCUCCUUGCAGAUCUCCAUGCUUUCUGCCAGGCUCACAGCUAUGAUGUCCUGGUUGCCAUGACUAUCUUUUUCAACACUCACAAUGAGCCAGUGCGGCAGUUGGCUAUUUUCUGUCCCCAUGUGGCACUCCAAACAACGAUCUGUGAAGUCCUGGAACGCUCCCACUCUCCACCCCUGAAGCUGACCCCUGCCUCAAGUACCCACCCUAACCUCCAUGCCUAUCUUCAAGGCAACACCCAGGUCUCUCGAAAGAAACUUCUGCCCCUGCUCCAGGAAGCCCUGUCAGCAUAUUUUGACUCCAUGAAGAUCCCUUCAGGACAGCCUGAGACAGCAGAUGUGUCCAGGGAGCAAGUGGACAAGGAAUUGGACAGGGCAAGUAACUCCCUGAUUUCUGGCCUGAGUCAAGAUGAGGAGGACCCUCCGCUGCCCCCGACGCCCAUGAACAGCUUGGUGGAUGAGUGCCCUCUAGAUCAGGGGCUGCCUAAACUCUCUGCUGAGGCCGUCUUCGAGAAGUGCAGUCAGAUCUCACUGUCACAGUCUACCACAGCCUCCCUGUCCAAGAAGUGACUGUUGAGAGGCGAGGAGGUAGUGGGUGAGGCUACCUGACUCACUUCAAAUGCAUGUUUUGAGAUGUUUGGAGAUUCAGCAAUUCUGUCUUCAUUGCUCCAGGAUCUGGUAUACUGUUCUCAUAAAACUGAGAGGAGAAAAAAAGUGAAAGAAAGCAGCUGCUUUAAGAAUGGUUUUCCACCUUUUCCCCCUAAUCUCUACCAAUCAGACACAUUUUAUUAUUUAAAUCUGCACCUCUCUCUAUUUUAUUUGCCAGGGGCACGAUGUGACAUAUCUGCAGUCCCAGCACAGUGGGACAAAAAGAAUUUAGACCCCAAAAGUGUCCUCGGCAUGGAUCUUGAACAGAACCAGUAUCUGUCAUGGAACUGAACAUUCAUCGAUGGUCUCCAUGUAUUCAUUUAUUCACUUGUUCAUUCAAGUAUUUAUUGAAUACCUGCCUCAAGCUAGAGAGAAAAGAGAGUGCGCUUUGGAAAUUUAUUCCAGUUUUCAGCCUACAGCAGAUUAUCAGCUCGGUGACUUUUCUUUCUGCCACCAUUUAGGUGAUGGUGUUUGAUUCAGAGAUGGCUGAAUUUCUAUUCUUAGCUUAUUGUGACUGUUUCAGAUCUAGUUUGGGAACAGAUUAGAGGCCAUUGUCUUCUGUCCUGAUCAGGUGGCCUGGCUGUUUCUUUGGAUCCCUCUGUCCCAGAGCCACCCAGAACCCUGACUCUUGAGAAUCAAGAAAACACCCAGAAAGGCCUUAAUGACCUCAUAGGCACUCUUCCAAAAAGACAACAGAACUGGAAUGAGAGGCCUGGGUCUGUCUCCUGCCUUAGCAGGCCUAUCAAUUUCUUGUCAAUCUCUUUUUUUCCUUGCUCACAUUAAAAGGAAGCAUGGAGUUCUAAUGCUCCCAUAAACUAUGUAUUUUGGCAAGACACUUCACUACUCCAGGUCUCACUUUCCCCAUCUGUAAAACAGGGUUUGGACUAGGUGUUCCCUGGUAUUCUGUGAUCUGCCUCUUGCUGCCAUUCUUUCUCUCCUCUGCUUCUCUGUAUUUUUCUUCUGUUAUCCCUGGGGGUGCUCAGGUUCACUUGAUUGUCUGUAUUUCUGUGUGGUUGUAGCAAGGACUCAGCCUCAUGUAGCACGAAUAGGGGUGUGGUUCAUGGCGUGUUGACCCAGCAGAGCACUCCCUCCCACUAACUUGUUCUGCAUGUGUAGAGUCUCCCCAUUUUUUUUAACGCAACCCUUUCCCCUUUUUCCUACCCCACAGCUCUGUUCCAUGUAAGUUGCCAACAGUUUCACUGAACAGUGGGGUAUGUGAUGGUUUUGGCAUGACAUCUUCAGUAUGAGGGGGACAGUUUGACUUCACUUUGAGGGUGUGAUGUCUGUAGCUAUGUGGAAGGUAAAAAUAGUGGUGUGAUCAUGAACCAAAGGAAUUUAUGUUUUGUAACUUGGGUACUUUAUUUUGCAUUUUGUUAUACUAUUAAAUAAUUUUUUCCUGUU